AUUGGUCGGCGUGCCGUCGCCCCGCUGGAGGGAGGACUCAGGCCCCGCUGGCCGCGGGCUCGGUACCCGGUGGGUCGGUGGAGCGUCUGUUGGGUCCGGGCCGCCGGCUUCGCCCUCGCCAUGGCGCCCUGGCUGCAGCUCCUGUCGCUGCUGGGGCUGCUCCCGGGCGCAGUGGCCGCCCCCGCCCAGCCCCGAGCCGCCAGCUUUCAGGCCUGGGGGCCGCCGUCCCCGGAGCUGCUGGCGCCCACCCGCUUCGCGCUGGAGAUGUUCAACCGCGGCCGGGCUGCGGGGACGCGGGCCGUGCUGGGCCUUGUGCGCGGCCGCGUCCGCCGGGUGAGGACGCGCCGGGGGCGGGGGCGCCAGGCCCGGGUCCAAGGGAUAGGAGCUUUGACCUAACAUUGGGAUGGGGCCUGCCCGCUGGACGAACCGAUCUCUGGCGGGUCAGGGGUCGCUGUACUCCCUGGAGGCCACCCUGGAGGAGCCACCCUGCAACGACCCCAUGGUGUGCCGGCUCCCCGUGUCCAAGAAAACCCUGCUCUGCAGCUUCCAAGUCCUGGAUGAGCUCGGAAGACACGUGCUGCUGCGGAAGGACUGUGGCCCAGUGGACACCAAGGUUCCAGGUGCUGGGGAGCCCAAGUCAGCCUUCACUCAGGGCUCAGCCAUGAUUUCUUCUCUGUCCCAAAACCAUCCAGACAACAGAAACGAGACUUUCAGCUCAGUCAUUUCCCUGUUGAAUGAGGAUCCCCUGUCCCAGGACUUGCCUGUGAAGAUGGCUUCAAUCUUCAAGAACUUUGUCAUUACCUAUAACCGGACAUAUGAGUCAAAGGAAGAAGCCCGGUGGCGCCUGUCCGUCUUUGUCAAUAACAUGGUGCGAGCACAGAAGAUCCAGGCCCUGGACCGUGGCACAGCUCAGUAUGGAGUCACCAAGUUCAGUGAUCUCACAGAGGAGGAGUUCCGCACUAUCUACCUGAAUACUCUCCUGAGGAAAGAGCCUGGCAACAAGAUGAAGCAAGCCAAGUCUGUGGGUGACCUCGCCCCACCUGAAUGGGACUGGAGGAGUAAGGGGGCUGUCACAAAAGUCAAAGACCAGGGCAUGUGUGGCUCCUGCUGGGCCUUCUCAGUCACAGGCAAUGUGGAGGGCCAGUGGUUUCUCAACCAGGGGACCCUGCUCUCCCUCUCUGAACAGGAGCUCUUGGACUGUGACAAGAUGGACAAGGCCUGCAUGGGCGGCUUGCCCUCCAAUGCCUACUCGGCCAUAAAGAAUUUGGGAGGGCUGGAGACAGAGGAUGACUACAGCUACCAGGGUCACAUGCAGUCCUGCAACUUCUCAGCAGAGAAGGCCAAGGUCUACAUCAAUGACUCCGUGGAGCUGAGCCAGAACGAGCAGAAGCUGGCAGCCUGGCUGGCCAAGAGAGGCCCAAUCUCCGUGGCCAUCAAUGCCUUUGGCAUGCAGUUUUACCGCCACGGGAUCUCCCGCCCUCUCCGGCCCCUCUGCAGCCCUUGGCUCAUUGACCAUGCGGUGUUGCUUGUGGGCUACGGCAACCGCUCUGACGUUCCCUUUUGGGCCAUCAAGAACAGCUGGGGCACUGACUGGGGUGAGAAGGGUUACUACUACUUGCAUCGUGGGUCCGGGGCCUGUGGCGUGAACACCAUGGCCAGCUCGGCGGUGGUGGACUGAAGAGGGGCCCCCAGCUCGGGACCUGGUGCUGAUCAGAGUGGCUGCUGCCCCAGCCUGACAUGUGUCCAGGCCCCUCCCCGGGAGGUACAGCUGGCAGAGGGAAAGGCACUGGGUACCUCAGGGUGAGCAGAGGGCACUGGGCUGGGGCACAGCCCCUGCUUCCCUGCACCCCAUUCCCACCCUGAAGUUCUGCACCUGCACCUUUGUUGAAUUGUGGUAGCUUAGGAGGAUGUCGGGGUGAAGGGUGGUAUCUUGGCAGUUGAAGCUGGGGCAAGAACUCUGGGCUUGGGUAAUGAGCAGGAAGAAAAUUUUCUGAUCUUAAGCCCAGCUCUGUUCUGCCCCCGCUUUCCUCUGUUUGAUACUAUAAAUUUUCUGGUUCCCUUGGAUUUAGGGAUAGUGUCCCUCUCCAUGUCCAGGAAACUUGUAACCACCCUUUUCUAACAGCAAUAAAGAGGUGUCCUUGUCCCGA